ACUCGGCCUUAAGCCGUCCUGGGUGUAUGUGAGGCUGAAAGGGAAGGAGGAACAGGGUCUGGGCCGCUGUGUGCUCUGCCGUCAUCUCUAAGAAACAACCAUACCACUGAAUGCUACUGUGUACUUACAAACCACACUCAUAUUCGUCACGUCAUUUCAUCUUCACCCCCACCUCCAAAUGAGGCUUGAAAUGAGAUGAGAUGUUCCUCCCUCCCCUUUCAACCAUGGACCUCACACUGUGGACUUCCUCUUAGAGCCUCUGAGUUAGGUACCCAAGCCAAGGCACAAUGUCCCUGCCCCCCAUAAGACUGCCCAGCCCCUAUGGCUCUGAUCGGCUGGUACAGCUAGCAGCCAGGCUCCGGCCAGCACUCUGUGAUACUCUGAUCACCGUAGGGAGCCAGGAGUUCCCCGCCCACAGCCUGGUGCUAGCAGGUGUCAGCCAGCAGCUGGGCCGCAGGGGCCAGUGGGCUCUGGGAGAAGGCAUCAGCCCUUCUACCUUUGCCCAGCUCCUGAACUUUGUGUAUGGGGAGAGUGUAGAGCUGCAGCCUGGAGAGCUAAGGCCCCUUCAGGAGGCGGCCAGGGCCUUGGGAGUGCAGUCCCUGGAAGAGGCAUGCUGGAGGGCUCGAGGGGACAGGGCUAAAAAGCCAGAUCCAGGCCUGAAGAAACAUCAGGAGGAGCCAGAGAAACCCUCAAGGAAUCCUGAGAGAGAACUGGGGGACCCUGGAGAGAAGCAGAAACCAGAACAGGUUUCUAGAACUGGUGGGAGAGAACAGGAGAUGUUGCACAAGCACUCGCCACCAAGAGGCAGACCCGAGAUGGCAGGAGCAACGCAGGAGGCUCAGCAGGAACAGACCAGGUCAAAGGAGAAACGCCUCCAAGCCCCUGUUGGCCAAAGGGGAGCAGAUGGGAAGCAUGGAGUGCUCACGUGGUUGAGGGAAAAUCCAGGGGGCUCUGAGGAAAGUCUGCGCAAGCUCCCUGGCCCCCUUCCCCCAGCAGGCUCCCUGCAAACCAGCGUCACCCCUAGGCCCUCGUGGGCUGAGGCCCCUUGGUUGGUGGGGGGCCAGCCUGCCCUGUGGAGCAUCCUGCUGAUGCCGCCCAGAUAUGGCAUUCCCUUCUACCAUAGCACCCCCACCACUGGAGCCUGGCAGGAGGUCUGGCGGGAACAGAGGAUCCCACUGUCCCUAAAUGCCCCCAAAGGGCUCUGGAGCCAGAACCAGUUGGCCUCCUCCAGCCCUACCCCAGGUUCCCUCCCCCAGGGCCCCGCACAGCUCAGCCCUGGGGAGAUGGAAGAGUCUGAUCAGGGGCACACAGGCGCACUUGCAACCUGUGCGGGUCAUGAGGACAAGGCAGGCUGCCCACCUCGCCCGCACCCUCCCCCGGCCCCUCCUGCUCGGUCUCGGCCCUAUGCGUGCUCUGUCUGUGGAAAGAGGUUUUCACUCAAGCAUCAGAUGGAGACGCACUACCGAGUCCACACAGGAGAGAAGCCCUUCUCCUGUAGCCUUUGUCCUCAGCGCUCCCGGGACUUCUCGGCCAUGACCAAGCACCUGCGGACACACGGGGCCGCUCCGUACCGCUGCUCCCUGUGCGGGGCCGGCUGUCCCAGCCUGGCCUCCAUGCAGGCGCACAUGCGCGGUCACUCGCCCAGCCAACUCCCGCCCGGAUGGACCAUCCGCUCCACCUUCCUCUACUCCUCCUCGAGGCCGUCUCGGCCCUCGACCUCUCCCUGUUGUCCUUCUUCCUCCACCACCUGACGGGGUGUCGGUAGCGUCUUAGCCAAGAGUCCAAUUAAAGAACGAAAAGCGGGCCGGCUCGGCUUCUGACCUGGCACCGCUGCUACGGCGGCCUAGCAAAUUCCGCCCCAGAAGCGCCCCAGGAAGGGCGCCGAGUGCCCUCUCCUGGACGAUCGCGGGUCGCAGAAGCCCAGGCCAGCGAGCCCUACAGAGUGAGGACACUGAAGUGUGCAGGAGCGAAGGUUAACAGUAGGGGAGAUUGUCGAUCUCAUCACCAUAAUAAAGAGUUUCCUGUGCCCUCCCUUCA